GGGGUUGGCCUAGGCGAAGAUCCGGACUCUGGGUGUUUUGCUACCGUGACCGUUUAGAAACAGAGUCUCGCUCUGUCGCCCAGGCUGGAGUGCAGUGUGGCCCGAUCUCAGCUCACUGCAACCCCCACCUCCCGGGCUCAAGAGAUCCACCCACCUCAGCUUCCCAAGUAGCUGGGACUACACGCGCCCGCCACCACAACCGGCUAAUUUUUGUACUUUUAGUAGAGACCAGGUUUCACCAUGUUGGCCAGGCAGGUCUCGAACUCUUGACCUCAAGUGAUCCGUCUGCCUCGGCCUCCCAAAGUGCUGGGAGUACAGGCGUGAAUCACCGCGCCCGGCCACAUUUGGUAUUUCUCUGUUUGUGUUAUAGAGACAGGGUCUUGCUCUGCCACCCAGGCUGGAGUGCAGUUGAAGCAGGAUAUUCCUCUGACCCCUUCGUGGGUCUUGCGGCUGCGGUGCCUCACUUACUUAGCCCACGGCUCUCAACUCCUCGCGGGAGGGGGGGCGCGAGUGAAUGAGGCGGGAACUGGAGUGCUGGAAGCCACGAACUCCAGUCACCCAGGCCUGCUGCGCUCCACCCUUUAUGGGAGGGUGCGUGGGGGUGAGCAGAUGCUGGAGCCGGAGCGAGCGCUUUUGGUCGCCGGUAGGAGCGAACUCCAUGCAGGCCCUGCGGCUGUGUCUAGGGGAUGCCCGCGACCCCUGAAGACCCACAGCCUGUCUUACAACCUGUCAUGGUUGUGAAAAGUUUUGAGAGAACGUCUGCACAGUGUCUAACGGUGUCUGGUAUAUAGUGUGCACUCAAAUGGUAACCAGUUUAGUUGCGAUAGUUGGUCUACCCCUCCAGGUGUUAACCUCUGCAGCUCCGUUUCCCUUCUAGACCCUAUUUCUGGGCCAUCGACUCCCACCAAUUAGGCAGGAAAAUACUGUUUGCCUCCAUCUGGCCCAAGGCUGUAUUCCUGGAGUUUAUGUGAGAACCUAACUCCUUUCUCAGCUCCAACUGUAACCCUCUCCCCACCUCCAACACACACAUAAACACUCACAUACACAUGCUACCACACUGCCUGCUGUGCCAUCAGCCUGCCUGAAGUUCACAUCAUUUUAGAAUUGGACGGGCCUUCAUAAUUUAAAUUUUAUUAUGAAAAAGUGAUAGUCUAAGGAACUCAUUUGAUUUUUUUGUCUAAAUGUCAAAUAUAGAGUAGAACGCACAAGUGUCUGUUAUAGAAAUACUUGAGAGUCCUAUAUGCACUGUUAUCCACAACCAUUUAAGCACUUAUCCACUAAUCCCUAAUAAGUACCCCUAAUAAGUACAUUUCUAAACCAGUUAUUCAAGCUACAUCCUCCCAAGAUUGGACUUUGUUUCUACUUUGGUAGGGACAUAAAUAAACGGAAACAACUGACCUAACUUUUUACUAAAGAGAUAAUAAAGGGAAUAAAAUUAAGAUUACAUUUGGAUUUUAACUUGUGUUCUUAUUCCUACUGCCAGCAAAAAUAUGUAAAGUGUUUUUAUCAUUAUAAAUGAAUAUACUAUUCAUUGUGCAGAUUUUGACAUGUUCAUAAAUAAGUUAGUACCCAAUGUUUGCUUGAUAAAGAAUGUGAUAAAAUGUUAACAUUUGGGAAAUCUGGGUGAAGAAUGUAUAGGAAUUAUUUGUAUGUAAUAUUUGUCAAUCUGAAAUUAUUUAAAAGAAAAAGUUAAACUGUCUCAUUCCUGAACAAUUAUAAAUUAUUCAACCCAAAACUGAAGGGGGCCUGCCCCUCCACACCUGUGGGUAUUUCUCGUCAAGUGGGAAGAGAGACUGAGAAAAUAAAUAAGACACAAAGUAUAGAGAAAGAACAGUGGGCCCAGAGGACGGGCACACUCAGUAUGCGAGGACCUGCACCGGCACUGGUAUCUGAGUUCCCUCAGUAUUUAUUGAUUACUUUUCACUAUCUCGGCAAGGGAACUGCGGUGGGAGAACAGGGUGAUGGUGGGGAGAAGGUCAGCAGGAAAACAUGUGAGUAAAGAAAUCUGCGUCAUAAAUAAGUUCAAGGGAAGGUACUGUGCCCAGAUGUGUAAGUAGGCUAGAUUCAUGUUUCUCUUUACCCAAACAUCUCAGUGUAGCAAAGAGUAACAGAGCAGUAUUGCUGCCAGCAUAUCUCCCCUCCAGCCACAGGGUGGUUUUCUCCUAUCUCAGAAUAGAACGAAUAGUCGGCUUUACACGGAGACAUUCUGUUCCCAGGGAUAUGCGGGAAACAGAGGCCUUCCUCUUUUACUAAUCCUUCUCAGCACAGACCCUUUAUGGGUGUCAGGCUGGGGGACGGUUAGGUCUUUCCCUUCCCACGAGGCCAUAUCUCAGGCUGUCUCAGUGGGGGGAAUUCUUGGACAAUACCCACGCUUUCUUGGGCAGAGGUCCCUGCAGCUUUCUGCAGUGCAUCAUGUCCCUGGUUAAUAGAGAAUGGAGAAUGGCGAUGACUUUUACCAAGCAUACAGUCUGCAAACAUAUUGUUAACAAGGCACAUCCUGCACAGCCCUAAAUCCCUUAAACCUUGAUUCAAUACAGCACAUGUUUCUGUAAGCACAGGGUUGGGGCUAAAGUUACAGAUUAACAGCAUCUCAAAGCAAAACAAUUUUUCUUUGUGCAGAUCAAAACGGAGUUUCUUUUGUCUUCCUUUUCCACAUAGACACAGUAACAGUCUGAGCUCUCUUUUCCCCACACAAAACUAUGUUUAAAAUAAUUUAAGUAUGAUUAUAUAAGAUUUGGGGGCCGGGUGCAGUGGCUCACGCCUGUAAUCCUAGCACUUUGGGAGGCCGAGGCAAGUGGAUUGCUUGAGCUCAGGAGUUUGAGACCAACCUGGGCAACAUGGUGAAACCCCGUCUCUACUAAAAUACAAAAAAUUAGCCGGGCAUGAUGGCACAUGCCUGUAAUCCCAGCUACUGGGGAGGAUGAGACAGGAGAAUUUCUUGAACCUGGGAGGCGGAGGUUGCAGUGAGCCGAGAUCAUGCCAUUGCACUCCAGCCUGGGUGACACAGCGAGACUCCGUCUCAAAAAUUUGGGACCGUUAAUAAACAGUUAUAUAUAUUUGGGAGAUUAGAUUACAUGUAUUAAAUCAAGAACAAUAAAAGCUGGUAUUUGAUAAAGUACUAAAGUAAAUAUAACAUCCUAAAUGUUUGCAAUAGAAUGAUUAUAGAGGAUAUGUUGUUGGAAAGUACCAGAACUAGAAACCCAGUUUCUAAGCAACCUGUGAAUCUUUGGAAAAUUAGAAAAAAAAAUUUGGAAGAAUAUUUCAAAUGGCUGAAGAUCACCGUUCCACUUGCUAAAUAGGCAUGUUAAGGGCAGAGGCCACUCAGAUUAAUGAAGUGUUCUAUUAACAGUUUUAACGAGAACUCCUGCAGUACUCUUAGAAACACCCUUAAGAGUCUUGUCUGUGUUCCCUGUUGUGAUUGGCUUGGAGUAGGAUACCUGUCUACCUCAUAUUACUUAUAUUUUUCCCUGUCUUCAUUUUAUCUCCCUCUGGUUGCAUACUUCAUCACUGAACACUUAAGAACAGAAACUGUUCAUACUUGGUGCGCUGUGGACUCUUGUGAUAAUUAACCAAGAGUAGCUCUAUUUGUCCAACCUCACACCUAAAGAAGAAAGAAAAUGGCUUGUGCUGAGUUUUCUUUUCAUGUACCAAGUCUUGAAGAGCUUGCUGGAGUUAUGCAGAAGGGGUUAAAAGAUAACUUUGCUGAUGUCCAGGUCUCUGUAGUUGAUUGCCCUGAUUUGACUAAGGAACCCUUUACCUUUCCUGUAAAAGGCAUCUGUGGGAAAACUAGAAUUGCAGAAGUUGGAGGUGUGCCUUACUUAUUGCCUCUUGUAAACCAAAAAAAAGUUUAUGAUCUGAAUAAAAUUGCAAAAGAAAUCAAGCUGCCUGGAGCCUUUAUUCUUGGAGCAGGAGCAGGUCCAUUUCAGACUCUCGGGUUCAAUUCUGAGUUUAUGCCAGUUAUUCAGACAGAAAGUGAACACAAGCCUCCUGUAAAUGGAAGUUACUUUGCCCAUGUGAACCCUGCAGAUGGAGGGUGCCUACUGGAGAAAUACAGUGAGAAAUGUCAUGAUUUUCAGUGUGCAUUACUGGCUAAUCUUUUUGCCAGUGAAGGCCAACCUGGCAAGGUAAUUGAGGUGAAAGCCAAAAGAAGAACUGGACCACUUAACUUUGUGACUUGUAUGAGAGAGACCCUGGAAAAACAUUAUGGAAAUAAGCCUAUAGGAAUGGGAGGUACUUUCAUAAUUCAGAAGGGAAAAGUGAAGUCUCACAUUAUGCCUGCAGAAUUUUCUUCCUGCCCCUUGAACUCUGAUGAAGAAGUGAAUAAAUGGUUGCAUUUUUAUGAAAUGAAAGCUCCUUUGGUUUGUCUACCAGUUUUUGUCUCCAGAGACCCAGGGUUUGAUUUGCGACUGGAGCACACUCAUUUUUUUAGUCGUCAUGGAGAAGGUGGACACUACCAUUAUGACACUACUCCAGAUAUAGUGGAAUAUCUUGGAUACUUCUUACCUGCAGAGUUUCUCUAUCGCAUUGAUCAACCAAAAGAGACGCAUUCAAUUGGGCGAGAUUAAAUCAGCUGAUACUUAUUUAGAAAAAGAAAUAAUUAAGGUUAAUUAAUUGAUUGACUUAUUAAUUAAUACUGAUAUAAAACCAAUAGAAAUGAUCCCACAGGCCAGGCACAAUGGCUCAUGCCUAUAAUCCCAGCACUUUGGGAGGCUGAGGCAGGAAGCACACUGGAGCCCAGGAGUUUGAGACCAGCUUGGGCAACAUAGCAAGACCCUGUCUAUUUUUUUAAAAAAGUAAAAAAUAGAAAUUAUCUCACUACUUAAAUCCCAUUUUUUUCACUUCAUAUGAAAGAACAUAUUGAUAGUAUAUUCUAUAUUAUUUCAUAGAUCUGUCUGAAAGAGAUUGGGAACAAAAAUAUCUAAUUGAGAUAUUCUUUAAUUUUUUACAUAGCAGCUUUAUUUUUUUUAUUCUGUAGUAUCAGCGAAAUCAGUCAUGUUUAUACCUUGAAUAUAAAUAUCAGGAAUCAUGCAAUUAUUUCUACUAUGUAUUUAGUAGUAUCUUAUAUUUGUAUAACAUUAUUACAUUUUGCAAAUUAGUAUCACAACUGCUAAGUAGAUGUUUCUGAGUAUUAGAAAAAUCAGUGUUAUUACCUGCAGGAUAUUAAAAAACAUUUGAAAAAGAGAAAAAGAAAAAUCAGUGUUUAGAAAUGUUGAUAGUUAUUGAAUCUUUGAAUUGAAUUUUAAAAAUCCAUUCUAGUAAUCAGAGUAUACUUUUUUUAUAGAACAAGGUGGCAGGUGGGGAGCCCUUUACCCUUCUGGUGAAGUUAAACCAUAGAAGUUUACAAUUUGCCUUUCACAAACAUUAGCAGUCCGGGCAUGGUGGCUGAAGCCUGUGAUCCCAGCAUGUUGGGAGGCCGAGUGGGAGGAUUGCCUGAGCCUAGGAGUUUAAACCAGCCUGGGCACCAUGGUGAGACCCCAUCUCUAUUAUUUAAAAUGUUUCUUAAAUAAAAAAAACACAAACAUUAGCAACUAGUUGGCUAGCCAUAAUUCCUCCCUUGUUUCGAUUGCCAGUUAGAAGCAAUUUUUAUUUCACUGGUUAUUUGCAAGAGAAGGGGUAAAAAAACAGCAUCAGAGUGCAACACUGAAGUGAGCUUACUUUAAUUUGUAAGUGAAGCUGUUGCUGAACAUGACCACUAUCGUUGCUGAAAUAUAAAAUUAUACUCACUGAUUGUAAUGGUUGAAAUUUUCCUGAAUAAUCAUUAGCCAAAGAUCAACUCUCUAAUGGUGCUAAUGGCAAUCUAGCUAAUGUGCAAAUUUAGGAAGUCUUCAGUACUAAGUACAUAAUUUUCAAAUAAUAUUUUUUAAUUGUCUACUUUGGAUGUUAGCUAUGUCUUGUGAGUAUAAAUUCCAAUUUUAAGCACUAUUUUGAUGCAAAAAAAUGAAUAAAAAAUUUAAUUUAUGAUAUGUUUGUAAUAUCUUACCUCCAGACAAAAUAAUAUUAAUAGUCUAUCAUUUAACAAAUAUGUAUUGAACACCUACCCUUCUCUCUGGAGUGUACACUUCAUGUGGGCAAGGGCCUUGUUCACGACUGUAGCACUAGUGCCUUUAACUGCUAGCAAAGUAGCCACUCGGAUGAUUAUACCAAACACUUUACUAAAGCUGGGGAUCUGUCUAGUGGGGAAGACAAACAAUAAAUAUAUAAUAUGUCAGGUGGUAUUAAAUGCUAUGAAAAGAAAGGAGUAGAUGGACUGUAAAGGAGGAUGCUAUUUUUUUGUGGCCAUCCCGCACUGAGACAGGAUGCAUUCCACACUCAAAAUUUGGUUCACAUGUCCAGACUGAUAGCCAAGUUCAGUGGCUCACGCCUGUAAUCCUAGUACUUAGGGAGACCAAGGCAGGAGGAUCACUUGAGGCCAGGAGUUCAAGGCCAGCCUGGGCAACAGAGAGAGACCCCCAUCUCUGCAAAAAAAGAAAAAAAAUUUUUUAAUUAUCUGGGCAUGGUUGUGCACACCUGUUGUCCCAGCUGCUCAGGAGGCUGAGGCACGAGAAUCACUUGAGCCCAGAAGUUGGAGGCUACAGUGAGCUAUGAUUGUUUCAUUGCACUGUAGCCUGGGCAACACAGUGAGACCCUGUCUCAAAAAGAAAAAAAAAAUGACUGAUGAAGCCACACACACACCAACAGAGUAUGAAAGGGUUGUUACUCACAUAAUGAAGCUUUCUGGGGAAAGCAGGGCAGCUCCUAAGCAGGAUUUGACAACAGGGAAGGAGACUGACUUGGAGUUUUUUGGUGGUUAGGGAGUAGGGCCAGAGUGAUGUUUCUUGCAUGUGGUUUGAAUUUCCCACUGGUAUCAAAGAAGGAAACACCCAGGCUUGCUUGCUUUAUUUUUUUAAAGAGAUGGUGUCUCACUAUGUUGCCCAGGCUGGGCUCAAGUCAUCUUCCUGCCUCGGCCUCCCAAAGUGCUGGGAUUACAGGCAUGGGCCACCAUGUCUGGCGAGCACCCAGGCUUUCUUAGCUUGCCAGAGGUGUAGGGCAUAAGGGGACGAGGGGUGGGAUAAGGCUUAAAAGCCACCAGCAGUCAAACAUAAAUUAAGUCAGAUUCUUAAUUACAGAUUUCAGAUCUGAUUUCAGAUCAGAGCUUAUUUCAGGUCAGAUUCCAGGUGUAGAGAUCAUCUGAAGCAGUCCUGGGCCUCUUCACACUACAGAUACCAACACUGCCUUUACUCUUCCAUUAGUGUCCUCCAAAAUGGGGUGCAUGGACAGCAGGUACACAUGACCUUCCAAGGGGUGUGGGAAUAUUAGAACAUCUAUUUAUAUAUUUUAUUUCGUCCUUUUAAGUUUCUGUGGUUUUGUGUACAUUUCUUACGUUAGGGAUUUCAGUUCAAAAUUGUAUUGCUGAUAGACACAAUUCAAAAAGCUUGGAGACCAGGUACAUUCACACCAUCUAAUAGAGAUGGGGGAAAAGAUCAAAAUGCUUUUCUUUUUAAAUUUUUUCUUAGUUUUCUUUCUUUAUAGAGACAGAGUUUCGCCGUGUUGGCCAGGCUGUUCUCGAACUCCUGGCCUCAAGUGAUCUGCCCGUCUCAGCCUCUCAAAUUGCUGGGAUUACAGGCAUGAGGCACUGCACCUCACCCA